CUCCAGACUGCCUUUGCACUCAAGACUACAAUGUCAGCUUUUCCCUGGGGUCUAACCUGCUGGCCUGCCCUGCAGAUAUUGACUUGCCAGUCCCCACAAUCAUGAGUCAGUUCUUUAAAAUAAAUCUUUCUCACUGUAUAUAUACAGCCUAUUGAUUCUAUUUAUCUAGAGAAUCUAGAGUAACAGAAUUUGGUACUGAGAGCAAUAGAACAGAAUUUUAAGGAUGAGUUUUAUGAAUUACUUCCCUAAUCUGAUAAGAUGUAAAGGCAUUAAUGACUUUUCAGUAGUGAAUAGAGUAUUAAUAAUUCAUAGUGUAAUGUGACAGUAGAGAUAUGCAAAGUAUUGCCAUUAGGUAAUCCUAUUCAGACAUUUACAAGAAGCAAGGUUCUGGGCAUCUGUAUUUGAUACCUUAGAACAUUUUUGAGUUCUCAUGAGAACAAUGAGAUUGGCUAGUUACUCCUAAUGUAGAGAAGGAAAGGAUGAUCUUAGGGAUUAAAUUUCCCAGCUCAAGUGCCGCAUGAAUAACCCAAAAGUUUCUCUUUCUGCCCUGAAAGAAACUCUUAUAUUUUAUAACAACAAAGCUGAGAUUAUUGAAAACCAAACCCAAAAUCUCAUCCUGAAAAUGGCUGAAUUACAGUGCAAAUUGAAUCCCCACCCUUUUAGGGUGUCUGCUGUUAAAAUGAGGGCAUUAACUGAGAAGGAAUGGGAUCUUGAAAACUGGAGUGCAGACAUAUGUGAAGAGCCUUAUAAAGCUGGGUGUAUCGAACCCCUUGACCCUGAUGAGUCUUCCUUGCCAGUAAAAGCAGCCAUGCCACCCCCAUCUGAGGAGAUUAAUGCUACUUUACCUGAGGAAACUUUUAUUACCUCCCCUGAGUUUGUUGCCUUGCAAGACAUUGCUGAUUCUUCUCAAGACUCACAGCUACCAUCCUUCAUUGCUUCUAGACCUAUAACUAGACUCAAGUCCCAGCAGGCCCUUAAAGGUCUCAUGAACAAAGUGGCCAUAAUGGCAGGGAUGGAGGUUAUGUAUGAGCUCAGCAACAUGGACUUCCACUCACCAAGGCUGACCUGGCUACAGCUGCUACUGAGUGUCCAAUCUGCCAGCAACAGAGACCAACAUUGAGUACCUGAUGGGCACUAUUCCAUGGGAUGAUCAGCCAGCUAGCUGAUGGCAGGUUGAUUACACUGGGACCACUUCCAUAAUGCAUGGAGCAGUGCUUUUUUCUUACUAGAAUAGACAGUAACUCUGGGUAUGGAUUUGCCUUCCCUGCACACAGUGCUCCCACCAAUUUACCAUCUGUGGACCUACAGAAUGCCUUAUCCACCAUCAUGGUAUUCCAUACAGCAUUGCUGUAAUCAAAGAACUCACUUUGUGGCAAAUACCUUGUGGCAAUGGCCUCAUUGCCACUAUGUUACCAUAUUCCUUAUCCUCUCAAAGCGGCUGGCUUGACAGAAUGGAUGAAUGGCCUUUUGAAGACUCAAUUACAGUGAAAGCUAGGUGGCAGUACCUUGCAGGGCUGGGGUAAUGUUCUUCAGGAGAUUAUACAUGCCCCAUGUCAGCAUCCAAUAUAUGAUGCUGUUUCUACCAUAGCCAAGAUUCAAGAAUCAAGGGGUGGAAAUGGGAGUGGCACCAGUUGCCAUUACCCCUAGUCAUCCAUUAGCAUAAUUUUUGCUUCCUGUUCCUGUUCCUGUGGCCUUAUGCUCUGCUGGUCUAGGGGUCUUAGUGGCUCUCUUCAUUAAUGUUGUCUGACACUUAGGCCUUUCUGUCUGCAAACUUGAGUCUUCCUUGAUGGACAACAGAGCAUGGAAUUAUUUUUGGACCAGAGUCUAGAUUUACCUAGUCUGUGGAGUCUAGAAGAUUGCUGCGUAAUAUGGAACAAGUUACUUUGUACAGAUUCUUUAUUUGAAAAGUAUGAAUAUAAUAGCACCUCCCUCAAAGGUUUGUUUUGGAGUUGACAAGGUGAUACAUGUAGCGUAUCAUGCUGCUUGAACCUGGUAUGCAUGUUUCACUGCAUUCUGUUAGUACUCCUGCUUCUGUUUAGGGAGCUUUCCUAUGAUCACUUGAAUUAUUUCUUUUCUGCAGUGAAUUCCACAGUUUGCUUCUGAAAUUCGUUUUUUACAUUCCCCUUGUAUGCACUGUGUCUUUUACCAUUUUAAUCAUUAUUGUAGGUUUUUUUAAUCUUUUUUUUCUGAGUUCUGGGAAAA